GCGGUGGCACUCACGGAAUCUCGGGUCUUCUGACGUGCCGGGCGGGAAGAUGUCAUCAUUGCCAAGAAGAGCGAAAGUACAGGUCCAGGAUGUGGUACUGAAAGAUGAAUUUUCUUCAUUCUCUGAGUUAUCAUCUGCCUCUGAAGAAGAUGACAAGGAAGAUAGUGCCUGGGAGCCCCAAAAGAAAGUUCCCAGAAGCCGUAAACAGCCCCCUCCCAAGGAAUCCAAACCAAAGAGGAUGCCUCGGGUGAAGAAGAAUGCCCCACAGAUCAGUGAUGGCUCAGAAGUCGUUGUUGUUAAGGAGGAGCUGAAUAGCUCUGUGGCUAUUGCUGAUACUGCUUUAGAAGACAGAAAAAAUAAAUUGGAUACUGUACAGACUCUGAAAACAGCCAAGACAAAACAGAAAUGUGCAGCGCAGCCACAUACAGUUCGAAGGACUAAAAAGCUGAAAGUUGAAGAAGAAACCAGCAAAGCCAGCAACUUAGAGGGUGAGAGUAAUAGUUCAGAGACACCAUCCACAAGCACUGUGUGGGGAGGUACAUGCAAGAAGGAAGAGAAUGACGAUGACUUUACAUUUGGUCAGUCCGCUUUAAAGAAAAUCAAGACUGAGACAUAUCCUCAGGGGCAGCCUGUCAAGUUUCCAGCAAAUGCCAAUAGUACUAAAGAGGAGGUGGAAAUGAAUUGGGACAUGGUACAGGUUUUAUCUGAGAGAACUAAUAUUGAACCUUGGGUUUGUGCCAACAUCAUUCGUCUCUUUAAUGAUGAUAACACAAUUCCCUUCAUUAUACGUUAUAGAAAAGAGCUCAUUAAUAACCUUGAUGCUGAUUCCUUGAGAGAAGUUCAGCAAACCCUAGAAGAGCUACGGGCUGUUGCAAAGAAAGUUCAUAGUACAAUCCAGAAAAUUAAGAAGGAAGGGAAGAUGUCUGAGUGCUUGUUAAAAGCCAUGCUGAAUUGUAAAACUUUUGAAGAACUAGAACACGUGUCUGCUCCAUAUAAAACUGGAAGCAAAGGGACUAAAGCCCAGAGAGCAAGACAGUUGGGCUUAGAAGGAGCAGCCAGGGCACUGCUUGAGAAACCAGGGGAGCUCAGUCUGCUAUCGUACAUUAGGCCUGACGUUAAAGGGCUUUCAACGCUUCAGGAUAUUGAAAUAGGAGUGCAGCAUAUUUUAGCAGAUAUGAUUGCUAAAGACAAAGACACGCUUGACUUCAUUCGGAACUUGUGCCAGAAGAGACAUGUUUGUAUCCAGUCAUCUCUGGCAAAAGUAUCCUCAAAAAAGGUAAAUGAGAAAGAUGUUGAUAAGUUUCUGCUCUACCAGCAUUUUUCCUGCAACAUAAGAAACAUUCACCAUCAUCAGAUUCUGGCAAUUAACCGUGGAGAAAAUUUGAAGGUACUGACGGUUAAGGUCAAUAUUUCUGAUGGAGUGAAGGAUGAAUUCUGUAGGUGGUGCAUCCAAAACAGGUGGAGACCACGUAGCUUUGCAAGGCCAGAGUUAAUGAAGAUCUUAUAUAAUUCACUGAAUGAUUCCUUUAAACGCCUUAUUUAUCCUCUUCUCUGUAGAGAAUUCAGAGCCAAACUAACAUCAGAUGCAGAGAAGGAAUCAGUAAUGAUGUUUGGACGGAACCUUCGUCAGCUCCUUUUAACAAGCCCUGUUCCAGGGCGCACCUUAAUGGGAGUGGAUCCUGGUUAUAAACAUGGUUGCAAAUUAGCUAUAAUUUCUCCUACUAGUCAGAUACUUCAUACUGAUGUGGUUUACUUGCAUUGUGGACAAGGCUUCCGAGAGGCGGAGAAAAUAAAGACACUUUUGCUGAAUUUCAACUGCAGCACAGUAGUGAUUGGAAAUGGAACUGCCUGCAGGGAAACAGAAGCUUACUUUGCUGACCUGAUAAUGAAGAAUUAUUUUGCACCACUGGAUGUUGUUUACUGUAUCGUCAGUGAAGCAGGAGCAUCAAUCUACAGUGUCAGCCCUGAAGCUAACAAAGAGAUGCCAGGGCUGGACCCUAAUUUGAGAAGUGCAGUUUCCAUAGCAAGGCGUGUACAAGAUCCAUUAGCUGAGCUAGUGAAAAUUGAGCCAAAGCACAUUGGAGUUGGAAUGUAUCAGCAUGACGUAUCCCAGACUUUACUCAAGGCAACACUGGACAGUGUUGUAGAAGAAUGUGUCAGCUUUGUGGGAGUGGAUAUUAACAUCUGUUCAGAAGUUUUGUUAAGGCAUAUUGCAGGACUCAAUGCCAACAGGGCCAAAAAUAUUAUUGAAUGGCGAGAGAAAAAUGGACCCUUUAUCAACCGAGAACAGCUGAAGAAAGUGAAAGGGCUGGGCCCAAAAUCCUUCCAACAGUGUGCUGGCUUCAUCAGAAUCAACCAGGAUUAUAUCCGAACGUUUUGCAGUCAGCAAACUGAAACUUCAGGCCAAAUUCAAGGAGUUGCUGUGACAUCUUCAGCAGACGUUGAGGUCACAAAUGAGAAGCAGGGCAAAAAGAAGAGCAAAACUGCAGUGAAUGUUUUACUGAAGCCAAAUCCUUUGGACCAAACUUGUAUUCAUCCAGAAUCAUAUGACAUAGCAAUGAGGUUUUUGUCAUCCAUUGGAGGGACACUGUAUGAGGUUGGAAAGCCUGAAAUGCAACAAAAAAUAAAUUCAUUCCUUGAAAAGGAAGGAAUGGAGAAAAUUGCAGAAAGAUUGCAAACAACAGUACACACCUUACAGGUCAUCAUAGAUGGUCUCAGCCAGCCUGAAAGCUUUGACUUUCGAACAGAUUUUGAUAAACCUGAUUUCAAGAGAAGCAUAGUAUGCCUGGAAGAUCUGCAGAUUGGGACAGUUCUUACAGGCAAAGUUGAGAAUGCCACUCUCUUUGGAAUUUUUGUGGAUAUAGGAGUGGGGAAAUCUGGGCUGAUUCCCAUACGAAAUGUAACAGAAGCAAAACUUUCAAAAACAAAGAAGAGAAGAAGCCUUGGACUGGGCCCCGGAGAAAGAGUGGAAGUCCAAGUACUCAACAUUGACAUCCCCCGAUCUAGGAUUACUCUGGACCUCAUUCGGGUGUUAUGAGUAUCCCACGAAGGCCAGACGCUGAUUUUAUUUUCUCAUUUCCACAGAUUGACAAGGAUAAGUCAGUUGUUUGUAAACUCUAGGUAGCAGAUGAGAAAUAAUUCACUUAAUAUCAGAAAUAUUUUCCAAACACUUUCCUUUAUUUUUUCUUCUGAAUAAAUAGAAAACCAACAGUUUGAUUUCCUUUUCCCUUAAAGGAAACAACUAAUACACAUUCUUAUAUGGCUUUAUGUAGUAAUAGUUUUCUGACUAAAAUUUUGUUUUUUAUUUUUUGUAAUUUAUCUUUAACUCCUUUUGCAUUUUGUAUAACAGAUUGCUUAACUUCUACUUGCCAACAUCUGCCUUGCUGGACUUGUAUGGGAUUGUCUUCUUGAUUUGAAUUGUACCGUCUUUGUUGACACAGUAGGGCUGGGCAGUGUUUAAUCCUUCCAUUUUAUAGAUUUUUUUUUAAUCAGGCCUUUUGGACUUCAUUCAUAAUUUUGCAAUAAUCUCUUUUCCCUUGUCAUGCAAGCCAAAAAUAUACCAGUAAAACAGAUUCUGACGUGUUUGUAGUUAUCAAAUGAAUGGCUCGAAACACUUCUCAAAAGGAUAUACGUAUUGACCCCAACAAUAAAUGUUUGUGGCUAGUGA